ACCACGUGGUCGCCUGGGGCUGGCAGAACCGCACGUUGGGGGGAGUUGGAGGGACGGGAGCACGGCAGGCCCGGGCCACAGCAGGUCUGGGUGCCACUGGGGCAGGAGCAGCCUCUGUCCCAGUCGUCCCGCGCCGUCAGGAGGUGGACACGGGGUUUUCCCUGGACACCAUCAGGAGGUGGACAUCGGGUUUGCCCUGAGCCCCAUCAGGAGGUGGACACGGGGUUUUCCCUGUGCCCCAUCAGGAGGUGGACACCACGUUUGUCCUGAGCCCCAUCAGGAGGUGGACAUUCGGUUUGCCCUGUGCCCCAUCAGGAGGUGGACACGGGGUUUUCCCUGAGCCCCAUCAGGAGGUGGACACUCGUUUUGCCCUGUGCCCCAUCAGGAGGUGGACACGGGGUUUGUCCUGAGCCCCAUCAGGAGGUGGACACGGGGUUUUCCCUGAGCCCCAUCAGGAGGUGGACACGGGGUUUGUCCUGAGCCCCAUCAGGAGGUGGACACGGGGUUUGUCCUGAGCCCCAUCAGGAGGUGGACACGGGGUUUGUCCUGAGCCCCAUCAGGAGGUGAACACCGGGUUUUCCCUGAGCCCCAUCAGGAGGUGGACACAGGGUUUGUCCUGAGCCCCAUCAGGAGGUGGACACGGGGUUUGUCCUAAGCCCCAUCAGGAGGUGGACACGGGGUUUUCCCUGCACACCAUCAGGAGGUGAACACCGGGUUUUCACUGAGCUCCAUCAGGAGGUGGACACGGGGUUUGUCCUGAGCCCCAUCAGGAGGUGGACACGGGGUUUUCCCUGAGCCCCAUCAGGAGGUGGACAUGGGGUUUUCCCUGAGCCCCAUCAGGAGGUGGACACUCGGUUUGUCCUGAGCCCCAUCAGGAGGUGGACACCGGGUUUUCCCUGAGCCCCAUGAGGAGGUGGACACUCGGUUUGUCCUGAGCCCCAUCAGGAGGUGGACACUCGGUUUGCCCUGUGCCCCAUCAGGAGGUGGACACUCGGUUUAUCCUGAGCCCCAUCAGGAGGUGGACACUCGGUUUGCCCUGUGCCCCAUCAGGAGGUGGACACUCGGUUUCUCCUGAGCCUCAUCAGGAGGUGGACACGGGGUUUUCCCUGAGCCCCACACUCGGUUUGUCCUGAGCGCCAUCAGGAGGUGGACACUGGGUUUGCCCUGUGCCCCAUCAGGAGAUGGACGCUCGGUUUCUCCUGAGCCCCAUCAGGAGGUGGACACGGGGUUUGCCCUGAGCCCCAUCAGGAGGUGGACACCGGGUUUGCCCUGAGCCCCAUCAGGAGGUGGACAUUCGGUUUGCCCUGAGCCCCAUCAGGAGGUGGACACCGGGUUUGUCCUGAGCCCCAUCAGGAGGUGGACAUUCGGUUUGCCCUGAGCCCCAUCAGGAGGUGGACACCGGGUUUGUCCUGAGCCCCAUCAGGAGGUGGACACUUGGUUUGCCCUGUGCCCCAUCAGGAGGUGGACACUUGGUUUGCCCUGUGCCCCAUCAGGAGGUGGACACCGGGUUUGCCCUGAGCCCCAUCAGGAGGUGGACACCGGGUUUGCCCUGAGCCCCAUCAGGAGGUGGACACGGGGUUUGUCCUGAGCCCCAUCAGGAGGUGGACACUCGGUUUGUCCUGAGCCCCAUCAGGAGGUGGACACCGGGUUUGCCCUGUGGCUUCUUGAUUCAUUUUCAGUUUUUUCCCAGAGAGCAGGUCCUCGGGAUGCCAGCUUUUGUGGCGGGGGUGGAGUAAGGUGCUUCCCCCGGCCCCAGUUGCGCGGCGGUCUUCACACGGGCGGUCUCGGCAUUGCCCGCGGCCUGGCUUUGGUCCAGCAGUGAGCAGCCUUUGGGCAGCUUUCCUGAUUCUUGUUUGCUCAGGAGACCCACAGGCUCCUCCGUGAUGAGAACUAGGUUGGUCUGGCUUCUACUUGUAGCCAGGGAUCAGUGAUUCAGAGCAGCUUUUCCCUGAAGACAGACGAAGAAGCUGGGCCCCCAGGAGCUCACAGGAUAGGGCCAGGCCCAGGCUGCAGCCUGGAGAGGCCUAUAACCUGCAGGAACGGGCGGGCCUUGCCAACUCUGGCCUGGGGUGUUGGCUGUUCUGGAAGAAGUAGCUGAGAGGCUGAAUUUGGCUUUGGUGGCAUCACUGGCCUGCUGGGUGUGGGGCCCUGCCGGGAUAUCCAUGGCCUGAAAGGUGACAUCUGGAGUGAGGGUGACCUGGACUCUGACGCGCCACACGAUCGGCACCCAGCCUGCUGAUGUCCAGGAAACCUUGAAUCUGGAUUUUUGGGGACCCCGCACUGCCGGCCCCAGGUGCCUGGCAAAAGAAGUAAGACGGCCCCUUUAGAGGAAGACAGCGUCAGCCGAGGCCUCGGGUCAUUUCUACAAAUCACCAUCUGGUGCGGGGUCCAUCACAUGCAAACAGAGGUAACCAGGCAGUCAAGGAGAUGCGCAAAACGCAGAAGCCAGGGAAGCAGUGCCACCCGCAGGAGCUCCCCGUGCUGCCCACGAGCCGAUCACCCCAGCCCAGCCCCCAGGAGGCUGGGCCAGACACCGACGAAGAGCUGAUGACUCUGGAACGGGGCGUAGCAGCGUUAGGGGAGAAAAUGAGAUGCGGAUCUGAGAAAACGGCGAAGCUGAUCGGUGGAACUGAGGGGCGGGUUUACCAGCUGACCAGGCGGCAGCGGACAGGAGGGAAGGAGAGAACGCGGGAGAGGGCGAGAUGAGGAAGGGUCGCUCUUGCAGAAACUUCAGAACAGGAGAGGGAAGGGGUUGGAAGUGAUGAUGACAGCAAAACCCUUUCCAAAAUGGACGGAAGAAAAUCUGAUGUUAAAAAUGCGCGUGGUCUGCCGGGAGCGUCUGCUGGGGCGUUCGCUCUGGAAGAUUCUUCAUGGUUUCUCACACGGGUAGAUGCGUGCUUGUAAUGCAGCCCAGUGGCCACACUCCUUUAUCCCGGAGACUCGGAAUGCGCGUCCACACACAGACCUGCACGUCAUGCUCCCUAGCAGCUUAACUCACCAUAGCCCAAACCAGAAGGACGCCCCCCACCGGCUGUCCUUCAGUGGGUGAGUGGCCAGGCAAAUGCUGGCCACCUCCCUCGGUGUCCUCCUCAGCAACAGGCAUGAACGCUGGGUCCCUGCCACACCCUGGGUGAUCUCGGCAGCAUGAUGGCGAGUGAAGAAGCUGGUUUCAAGGGGUGCACACUGUAUGAUCUCUUCAUCCCCAGGUGAUAGGAUUAGCGUGACGGAAACAGUGGCCCGGGGUGUAGGUGGGGGGGCCGCCGGCAGGCCGGUGUCUGGAAUCGGCACAUGGGCACGUUGGCACGUCACGUGGGCAUGUCCACACGCAUGCAAGGGGCUGUGGGUGAACUGCCCGUGGUGCACACCUGAGGGAGUUGUGUGGCACCAGCUCGGUUUGGACAGUGCCCUUUGUUAGGUACGGUUUUCUCAUUGGGAAGCUGGAUUUGUAUUAAAGAUGCACACGUAAGAAUAAAAAAGAGGCUCGUAGAAAACUUUUGGUGUCGUAAACAAUACUCAAACAGUUUUGCCAACAAAUUGGAAAGCUAAGGCAAAACAGAUGUUUUUCUAAAAUUGCAGUAAUCCCAAACUGCCUUGACAGGUUCAUAUAAAAUGCAGAUCAGUGGUUGGGGUGGGGCCGGCGUGGGCCCUGGCAUGAGACAGACUUCCUGCUCCCCACCCAGGCUGCACAGCCCAGGGCAGAGAAAGGACAACAUAAAUACACAGAAAACUGCCCCAGGGGAUGCAGCUGGAUUCUUGGAAGAGACGAGAGUGUUGGGAACCGUCCUGGCAUCCUGGAGGGGCCUGAAGCAGCCCCUAACCAGAAGCAGAGCCGGCGCCACAGAAAGGAGCCCCCAAGAACUAGGAGAGCUUGAAAUUAAAAACAUGAGUGAAAAUCUCAUAAAAACAGGAAGCUCAAAGACACAGGGACAUUGCAGAAGCCAGAGAGGUGAAGAGAAGCCGUGACCUCCCGGGGCUGUGUGUGGAGUCUGCAGGGGCUGCCUGGAUGCCGAGUCCGCGUUUCGCAGUGUGUGGUCCUGUGGGAGGACUUGGCUGCCCACGCUUUCUUGCCACUAGGGGUGGCCAAAGGAUUGAGCUCCAGAACAGAGGGGAGCAGGGCCUCUCCCUGCCGUCCCCUCCUCGUCCCUGCUGGCUGGAACCCGGGGUAGCCACCUUGGACUGUGAGGGGAGCCACGUGCUGGGAACCGUGGAGCAACAAGGCAGGAGGCAGGGACCCUCGUGGCUGUGGAGAGGGCAGCGGGGCCGCAGGCUCCCUGUCUCCAGGCUUUGGCGUGGGAGGAAACUGAACACCUGCUUUGUGUGCCACUGUUAGUCAGGAAUUCUGCCUCCUGGGGCAGAAACUUCCCGCAUAGCUGGUUGGAGGUCGCCGCCGUCUGAGUGCCGUGGAGGGAGAGAACGUGAUACCGUCAGUGCGGUCACAGGAGGAGCGGGAAGAAUGUCGGGGCCUGGGAGGCGCCCCAGUGUUCAGGUUCAGGACUGGGAUUUUACUGAUACCACGGGUGGGGGAUGUCACCCACCGGGACACAAGACUCAGCCCAGCCCCACUCGCCUGCUUUGGAAUUUCCACAGGAGAAGGGUUUUCAGCCCAGCACUGCACAUCUGAUCAAACUGCUGAGCAAGAAAAAGGAAGCCCUGGAGCCUGGAGGCUGCGUCCGGUGUGGGCUGCGGGGCCUGGAGCGGCAGGGCGGCUCCGGGAGGGCACAGGACGCAGUGGCCUGCGAGGACCUGCAGCCAGCUGGACAGUUGCACUCCUGCAAGACAAGCAUCUCCACGCCUUGGGGGUGGGGAGGCCACCAGAAAGCUCCGCCAGACAGAGGUGCUGGGGCUGUGCAGGAAACGAAGUGAUUAGAAAUCCCGGAAAAACACACAAGCAGGCGUUGUCAUGGUGACUGGGAAAAACACACAAGCUGGCGUUGUCAUGGUAAUGGAGUGUAGGACAGGCCUGGAGCCCCUCGGUCUCUUGCUGGCGGCUGGCACAGAGACGGGCUGCCGUGGGCUCUGACCUUAAUACCGGGUCACAGUCGCUUCUAGGACCAAGAGGACAGAGACCCCAUCACCGUAUGCAGGGGCCUGUUUCCAGGCAGACUGCCCAGUGCCCAGCUGAGCCUCGGGUGCAGUGCGACCCCCGCAGGGCAUGUCCAGACCCCAGGACCCCCUCUCAGGUCUAGAAGAUCCAGUUGGGCAGUGUUGGUACCACCAAGAGUAGACAGGACAGAGGAUCAGAGACAAUCCCACCCAGCAGGACCCAAGGACUCAGGCAGUGGCUUUUCAGGUGUGUGGGCCGAGGACUGGGGAGUCGGUGAAUUCUGGGGCCCCUGGGGUGGCCGUUCAGGAACUGCAGCAGCUCCCCCCACCACAGAUGCUCGCUGCCUACUGAAGCGGCCACGUGUUUGAAUGAAGAGCAGUUAGAGGAACGCUUGCAAGAGAAUGUGUUUAUUACCUGAGGUUAUGACAAUACAGAACAUACAAUGUUUUCUGUGGAAAAUGUGAUACUACAGAGGAAAAGGUCACUUUAAUUAAAUGGCAAUUAGAAGUAACAGCAUUGCAAGGUGGGGUGCAGCAGCUCACGCUUAUAAUCCCAGCACUUUAGGAGGCUGAGGCGGGUGGAUCACUUGAGGUCAGGAGUUCAAGACCAGCCUGGGCAACAUGGUGAAACCUCGUCUCUACUAAAAAUAUAGAAAUUAGCCACGCGUGGUGGUGCGCGCCUGUAGUCCAAGAUACUCAGGAGGCUGAGGCAGGAGAACCUCUUGACCCUAAGAGGCAGAGGUUGCAGUGAGCCAAGAUCGUGUCACUGCACUCCAGCCUGGGCAACAGAGCAAGACUCUGUCUCAAAAAGGAAAAAAAGAAAGAAUGACAUAGCAAAAUAAAUUUAAAAAAUAAAAACGGGAGAGGUAGGGGUUGGGUAUUUUCAAUUUGUGUGCCAGCCUAAGGGUGAAUGUCUGAUAACACUCAGAGCUGGUGCAGGGGCUGUGCCUGUCAUCCCAGCGUAUCCAGAGGCCAAGGCCAGAGGAUCGCUUCAGCCUAGGAGGUCAAGGCUGCAGCGAGUCAUGAUUACACCACUGCAGUCCAGCGAGGUCCUGUCUGUAAAAUAAGUAAAUGAAAAAGUUUAUAUAUUCAAAGACUCCUCCCAAUCAGUAGAAACAGAAAAAUCCCGACAGAAAAUGGAUGAGGGCGGUGGCGUUUGGUACAGACAGAGCGGUGUAUGAGAACCGGGGUGCGCCUCCUGGGUUCUCACAGGUGCAGCAGGCACCGCCGGUAACCCCUGGCCUGGCCUGCGCUGAGCCCUGCACCAGCCGUGCUGAGGGAGCCUGGGCCUGGCCCUUCAUGUGGGAUAGAAACGGCCGUGCCGGUCUCGAUGGUGCUUUGGCAGUUUCUCUGGAAAUCUGAAACCUGCGGUCUUCAGCCCAGCCCCACCCUGGGCCUGCAUGUGGCUGCGUGUCGUAGAGAAACAUCUGCCCUGAUGGUGACCUGAUGUGAGCAGCAGUUUCACAGAGUAAGCCACCCCUGUGCACGAGGUCUGGAAAGGUAAGUGCGACGUCGAGUCCUGAGCACAGAAGCAGGUGGCAGAACUGCAUGGCAGGAGGUGGGCUUGGCGGGCCCCUUCCUGACCCCCAAGAGCCAGCUGCCACCAGGAGCGUCCUGGGGUCUGUUUCCAGCCCGGUGGCAGCCGAGCUUCCUGGGCACCCAGCUUUCCCCAGCCUGCUCUGAGCACUGGAGUUGAGGGCACUGAGCAGAGUGGGGCUGAGCCCCUGGCGGUGGAGGGGACACAUCAGUGGGUGUUGGCUUGAGGUGGUUUCUGGGAGGCUGCUGGGCCCCGAUCUAAAGGGACACACCUGGCUGCACCCACCUCCUGCAGACUUUCUCCGUGGGAGACCAAUGCAACAGGCGGGGUGGAGCAGCCACGUGGCAGCCACGAGGGGGAAAGGAAGGUAGACCCUGAGGCUGAGCCGCUGUGGCACCCUGGCCUGUGGACCUGUGGAUGACGUGGCCGCCACGUGGUAAAGCGCACAUGCUAGCAGCUGUGGCCCUGCAGCUGAGCACAGGCCAACCUGGUCCUGAACGAGGCUGUGGGGGCCCUGAUGUACCACACCAUCACUCUCACCAGGGAGGACCUGGAGAAGUUCAAAGCCCUCCGCAUCAUCGUCCGGAUUGGCAGUGGUUUUGACAACAUCGACAUCAAGUCGGCCGGGGAUUUAGGCAUUGCCGUCUGCAACGUGCCCGCGGCGUCUGUGGAGGAGACGGCCGACUCGACGCUGUGCCACAUCCUGAACCUGUACCGGCGGGCCACCUGGCUGCACCAGGCGCUGCGGGAGGGCACACGAGUCCAGAGCGUCGAGCAGAUCCGCGAGGUGGCGUCCGGCGCUGCCAGGAUCCGCGGGGAGACCUUGGGCAUCAUCGGACUUGGUCGCGUGGGGCAGGCAGUGGCGCUGCGGGCCAAGGCCUUCGGCUUCAACGUGCUCUUCUACGACCCUUACUUGUCGGAUGGCGUGGAGCGGGCGCUGGGGCUGCAGCGUGUCAGCACCCUGCAGGACCUGCUCUUCCACAGCGACUGCGUGACCCUGCACUGCGGCCUCAACGAGCACAACCACCACCUCAUCAACGACUUCACCGUCAAGCAGAUGAGACAAGGGGCCUUCCUGGUGAACACAGCCCGGGGUGGCCUGGUGGAUGAGAAGGCGCUGGCCCAGGCCCUGAAGGAGGGCCGGAUCCGCGGCGCGGCCCUGGAUGUGCACGAGUCGGAACCCUUCAGCUUUAGCCAGGGCCCUCUGAAGGAUGCACCCAACCUCAUCUGCACCCCCCAUGCUGCAUGGUACAGCGAGCAGGCAUCCAUCGAGAUGCGAGAGGAGGCGGCACGGGAGAUCCGCAGAGCCAUCACAGGCCGGAUCCCAGACAGCCUGAAGAACUGUGUCAACAAGGACCAUCUGACAGCCGCCACCCACUGGGCCAGCAUGGACCCCGCCGUCGUGCACCCUGAGCUCAAUGGGGCUGCCUAUAGCAGGUACCCUCCGGGCGUGGUGGGCGUGGCCCCCACUGGCAUCCCAGCUGCUGUGGAAGGUAUCGUCCCCAGCGCCAUGUCCCUGUCCCACGGCCUGCCCCCUGUGGCCCACCCGCCCCACGCCCCUUCUCCUGGCCAAACCGUCAAGCCCGAGGCGGAUAGAGACCACGCCAGUGACCAGUUGUAGCCCGGGAGGAGCUCUCCAGCCUCGGCGCCUGGGCAGAGGGCCCGGAAACCCUCGGACCAGAGUGUGUGGAGGAGGCAUCUGUGUGGUGGCCCUGGCACUGCAGAGACUGGUCCGGGCUGUCAGGAGGCGGGAGGGGGCAGCGCUGGGCCUCGUGUCGCUUGUCGUCGUCCGUCCUGUGGGCGCUCUGCCCUGUGUCCUUCGCGUUCCUCGUUAAGCAGAAGAAGUCAGUAGUUAUUCUCCCAUGAACGUUCUUGUCUGUGUACAGUUUUUAGAACAUUACAAAGGAUCUGUUUGCUUAGCUGUCAACAAAAAGAAAACCUGAAGGAGCAUUUGGAAGUCAAUUUGAGGUUUUUUUUUUUGUUUUUUUUUUUUUUGUAUGUUGGAACGUGCCCCAGAAUGAGGCAGUUGGCAAACUUCUCAGGACAAUGAAUCCUUCCCGUUUUUCUUUUUAUGCCACACAGUGCAUUGUUUUUUCUACCUGCUUGUCUUAUUUUUAGAAUAAUUUAGAAAAACAAAACAAAGGCUGUUUUUCCUAAUUUUGGCAUGAACCCCCCCUUGUUCCAAAUGAAGACGGCAUCACGAAGCAGCUCCAAAAGGAAAAGCUUGGGCGGUGCCCAGCGUGCCCGCUGCCCAUCGACGUCUGUCCUGGGGACGUGGAGGGUGGCAGCGUCCCCGCCUGCACCAGUGCCGUCCUGCUGAUGUGGUAGGCUAGCAAUAUUUUGGUUAAAAUCAUGUUUGUGACUGUAACCAUUUGUAUGAAUUAUUUUAAAGAAAUAAAAAUCCUGGAAAGAGCCA